AUUCGAAAGGAAGGCGCCGGCUGCGGGAAGAUGGCGGCUCAGCCGCUGCGGCAUCGCUCACGUUGUGCAACGCCGCCCCGGGGGGACUUUUGUGGUGGCACUGAGAGGGCGAUUGACCAAGCUUCUUUUACGACCUCCAUGGAGUGGGAUACGCAGGUGGUGAAGGGGUCCUCGCCGCUCGGCCCCGCAGGGCUGGGGGCUGAGGAGCCAGCCGCCGGCCCGCAGCUGCCGUCUUGGCUGCAGCCUGAGAGGUGCGCUGUGUUCCAGUGCGCACAGUGUCACGCAGUGCUCGCCGACUCGGUGCACCUCGCCUGGGACCUGUCGCGGUCCCUCGGGGCCGUGGUCUUCUCCAGAGUUACAAAUAACGUCGUUUUGGAAGCGCCCUUCCUAGUUGGCAUUGAAGGUUCACUCAAAGGCAGUACUUACAACCUUUUAUUCUGUGGUUCUUGUGGGAUUCCCGUUGGUUUCCAUCUGUAUUCUACCCAUGCUGCCCUGGCUGCCUUGAGAGGUCACUUCUGCCUUUCCAGUGACAAAAUGGUGUGCUAUCUCUUAAAAACAAAAGCCAUAGUAAAUGCAUCAGAGAUGGAUAUUCAAAAUGUUCCUCUAUCAGAAAAGAUUGCAGAGCUGAAAGAGAAGAUAGUGCUAACGCACAAUCGCUUAAAAUCACUAAUGAAGAUUCUGAGUGAAGUGACUCCUGACCAGUCCAAGCCAGAAAACUGAUCCUGUACCAAAGCUUGAGUGUCAGGUUCAGGCUUUAUUGCUGUCUUCAACAACAGGUGCUGCUUAGUCAUUUCUUGAAAAAGAUUGGCUUCAAGAAUGGAGGGGAAAUGCAGUUUCUAUUUACCUUUAGGCUGAUUUUCCAAAUUAUUUGUGAAGCUGUUUUUAGAAGAUGAGAGACUAAGGAUUCUUCUCUUUUAUAGCUAUUUGCCUUAAGAACUUACUUUAGAUUCUUAUUGAAUUCAUAAUACUUAUCUCUGAAAAUGUCUUUGACUGUAAAUUUAGGAAUUAAGAUGCAGAGUCCCAUGUGUCCUCUGAUCUAAAGUUGCAUGGUUGGUCUGAAAAUAGAGUUGGGCUUAAUGUUGACUUCUAUUACUCCUGCAUGGAGCAGUUGUUAUGAAUACUAAUACAUCACUUUUUAACUUCUGUAAAAUACAGAUCAUAAUAUUCUAUAGGUAAUGUUUAAUAAAUUGCCUGAAUAAUA